AAAAGCUUUUACGAGGUAUCAGCACUUUUCUUUCAUUAGGGGGAAGGCGUGAGGAAAGUACCAAACAGCAGCGGAGUUUUAAACUUUAAAUAGACAGGUCUGAGUGCCUGAACUUGCCUUUUCAUUUUACUUCAUCCUCCAAGGAGUUCAAUCACUUGGCGUGACUUCACUACUUUUAAGCAAAAGAGUGGUGCCCAGGCAACAUGGGUGACUGGAGCGCCUUAGGCAAACUCCUUGACAAGGUUCAAGCCUACUCAACUGCUGGAGGGAAGGUGUGGCUGUCAGUACUUUUCAUUUUCCGAAUCCUGCUGCUGGGGACAGCGGUUGAGUCAGCCUGGGGAGAUGAGCAGUCUGCCUUUCGUUGUAACACUCAGCAACCUGGUUGUGAAAAUGUCUGCUAUGACAAGUCUUUCCCAAUCUCUCAUGUGCGCUUCUGGGUCCUGCAGAUCAUAUUUGUGUCUGUACCCACACUCUUGUACCUGGCUCAUGUGUUCUAUGUGAUGCGAAAGGAAGAGAAACUGAACAAGAAAGAGGAAGAACUCAAGGUUGCCCAAACUGAUGGUGUCAAUGUGGACAUGCACUUGAAGCAGAUUGAGAUAAAGAAGUUCAAGUACGGUAUUGAAGAGCAUGGUAAGGUGAAAAUGCGAGGGGGGUUGCUGCGAACCUACAUCAUCAGUAUCCUCUUCAAGUCUAUCUUUGAGGUGGCCUUCUUGCUGAUCCAGUGGUACAUCUAUGGAUUCAGCUUGAGUGCUGUUUACACUUGCAAAAGAGAUCCCUGCCCACAUCAGGUGGACUGUUUCCUCUCUCGCCCCACGGAGAAAACCAUCUUCAUCAUCUUCAUGCUGGUGGUGUCCUUGGUGUCCCUGGCCUUGAAUAUCAUUGAACUCUUCUAUGUUUUCUUCAAGGGCGUUAAGGAUCGGGUUAAGGGAAAGAGCGACCCUUACCAUGCGACCAGUGGUGCGCUGAGCCCUGCCAAAGACUGUGGGUCUCAAAAAUAUGCUUAUUUCAAUGGCUGCUCCUCACCAACCGCUCCCCUCUCGCCUAUGUCUCCUCCUGGGUACAAGCUGGUUACUGGCGACAGAAACAAUUCUUCUUGCCGCAAUUACAACAAGCAAGCAAGUGAGCAAAACUGGGCUAAUUACAGUGCAGAACAAAAUCGAAUGGGGCAGGCGGGAAGCACCAUCUCUAACUCCCAUGCACAGCCUUUUGAUUUCCCCGAUGAUAACCAGAAUUCUAAAAAACUAGCUGCUGGACAUGAAUUACAGCCACUAGCCAUUGUGGACCAGCGACCUUCAAGCAGAGCCAGCAGUCGUGCCAGCAGCAGACCUCGGCCUGAUGACCUGGAGAUCUAGAUACAGGCUUGAAAGCAUCAAGAUUCCACUCAAUUGUGGAGAAGAAAAAAGGUGCUGUAGAAAGUGCACCAGGUGUUAAUUUUGAUCCGGUGGAGGUGGUACUCAACAGCCUUAUUCAUGAGGCUUAGAAAACACAAAGACAUUAGAAUACCUAGGUUCACUGGGGGUGUAUGGGGUAGAUGGGUGGAGAGGGAGGGGAUAAGAGAGGUGCAUGUUGGUAUUUAAAGUAGUGGAUUCAAAGAACUUAGAUUAUAAAUAAGAGUUCCAUUAGGUGAUACAUAGAUAAGGGCUUUUUCUCCCCGCAAACACCCCUAAGAAUGGUUCUGUGUAUGUGAAUGAGCGGGUGGUAAUUGUGGCUAAAUAUUUUUGUUUUACCAAGAAACUGAAAUAAUUCUGGCCAGGAAUAAAUACUUCCUGAACAUCUUAGGUCUUUUCAACAAGAAAAAGACAGAGGAUUGUCCUUAAGUCCCUGCUAAAACAUUCCAUUGUUAAAAUUUGCACUUUGAAGGUAAGCUUUCUAGGCCUGACCCUCCAGGUGUCAAUGGACUUGUGCUACUAUAUUUUUUUAUUCUUGGUAUCAGUUUAAAAUUCAGACAAGGCCCACAGAAUAAGAUUUUCCAUGCAUUUGCAAAUACGUAUAUUCUUUUUCCAUCCACUUGCACAAUAUCAUUACCAUCACUUUUUCAUCAUUCCUCAGCUACUACUCACAUUCAUUUAAUGGUUUCUGUAAACAUUUUUAAGACAGUUGGGAUGUCACUUAACAUUUUUUUUUUGAGCUAAAGUCAGGGAAUCAAGCCAUGCUUAAUAUUUAACAAUCACUUAUAUGUGUGUCGAAGAGUUUGUUUUGUUUGUCAUGUAUUGGUACAAGCAGAUACAGUAUAAACUCACAAACACAGAUUUGAAAAUAAUGCACAUAUGGUGUUCAAAUUUGAACCUUUCUCAUGGAUUUUUGUGGUGUGGGCCAAUAUGGUGUUUACAUUAUAUAAUUCCUGCUGUGGCAAGUAAAGCACACUUUUUUUUUCUCCUAAAAUGUUUUUCCCUGUGUAUCCUAUUAUGGAUACUGGUUUUGUUAAUUAUGAUUCUUUAUUUUCUCUCCUUUUUUUAGGAUAUAGCAGUAAUGCUAUUACUGAAAUGAAUUUCCUUUUUCUGAAAUGUAAUCAUUGAUGCUUGAAUGAUAGAAUUUUAGUACUGUAAACAGGCUUUAGUCAUUAAUGUGAGAGACUUAGAAAAAAUGCUUAGAGUGGACUAUUAAAUGUGCCUAAAUGAAUUUUGCAGUAACUGGUAUUCUUGGGUUUUCCUACUUAAUACACAGUAAUUCAGAACUUGUAUUCUAUUAUGAGUUUAGCAGUCUUUUGGAGUGACCAGCAACUUUGAUGUUUGCACUAAGAUUUUAUUUGGAAUGCAAGAGAGGUUGAAAGAGGAUUCAGUAGUACACAUACAACUAAUUUAUUUGAACUAUAUGUUGAAGACAUCUACCAGUUUCUCCAAAUGCCUUUUUUAAAACUCAUCACAGAAGAUUGGUGAAAAUGCUGAGUAUGACACUUUUCUUCUUGCAUGCAUGUCAGCUACAUAAACAGUUUUGUACAAUGAAAAUUACUAAUUUGUUUGACAUUCCAUGUUAAACUACGGUCAUGUUCAGCUUCAUUGCAUGUAAUGUAGACCUAGUCCAUCAGAUCAUGUGUUCUGGAGAGUGUUCUUUAUUCAAUAAAGUUUUAAUUUAGUAUAAACAUA